AGCACUGCUUCCGGUCGGUGGCGCUUCUCUCUGGCCCGAGCCAGGUCAGUCCGGCAGUGCAGAUGGCCCAUCCCGGGCUCUGGGCUCCUAGACCGGGGUGGGCCCUGCCAGGAGUGGGCCUGAGCCUCGCACGUCCUCUGAAACUACGCUAUGCUCUGCUUUUGCGGCGCGAUGGGCGUGGGAGCGGGGGCUGCCCAAAGAUGGGCUGGGGUUGGAGGAAGUGGCCCGGUAGCCGCUGUGUGUCCUGAGGCCGUAAGGCGCCUGACCCCACCCCUGAAGCUGGCGACGGAGCAGGGCCUGUUUUCUCUACACUAUAGUCAUGAUCCGCUGGGCCCCCAGCGCAUCUCCUGGAAGAGCCCACUCACCCUGGACGAGCUCUUCGGUAGCCUCAGACCGUCCUUGAAGAGGAUGACUGAGACAUUAUGGGCCACGCGCUGUGUGUCUGCUCUCGGGGAACUGUCAUCAUUGACAAUAAGCGCUACCUCUUCAUCCAGAAACUGGGGGAGGGUGGGUUCAGCUAUGUGGACCUAGUGGAAGGGUUACAUGAUGGACACUUCUACGCCCUGAAGCGAAUCCUGUGUCACGAGCAGCAGGACCGGGAGGAGGCCCAGCGAGAAGCCGACAUGCAUCGCCUCUUCAAUCACCCCAACAUCCUUCGCCUCGUGGCUUACUGUCUGAGGGAACGGGGUGCUAAGCAUGAGGCCUGGCUGCUGCUACCAUUCUUCAAGAGAGGUACGCUGUGGAAUGAGAUAGAAAGGCUGAAGGACAAAGGCAACUUCCUGACCGAGGAUCAAAUCCUUUGGCUGCUGCUGGGGAUCUGCAGAGGCCUUGAGGCCAUUCAUGCCAAGGGUUAUGCCCACAGAGACUUGAAGCCCACCAAUAUAUUGCUUGGAGAUGAGGGGCAGCCAGUUUUAAUGGACUUGGGUUCCAUGAAUCAAGCAUGCAUCCAUGUGGAGGGCUCCCGCCAGGCUCUGACCCUGCAGGACUGGGCAGCCCAGCGGUGCACCAUCUCCUACCGAGCCCCAGAGCUCUUCUCUGUGCAGAGUCACUGUGUCAUCGAUGAGCGGACUGAUGUCUGGUCCCUAGGCUGCGUGCUAUAUGCCAUGAUGUUUGGGGAAGGCCCUUAUGACAUGGUGUUCCAAAAGGGUGACAGUGUGGCCCUUGCUGUGCAGAACCAACUCAGCAUCCCACAAAGCCCCAGGCAUUCUUCAGCAUUGCGGCAGCUCCUGAACUCGAUGAUGACCGUGGACCCGCAUCAGCGUCCUCACAUUCCUCUCCUCCUCAGUCAGCUGGAGGCGCUUCAGCCCCCAGCUCCUGGCCAACAUACUACCCAAAUCUGAAAAAGCAGCAUGUUGAGAAGAUGGCCCCUUGUGCCUUGGAAAGAGGUUCCCAUCCCUCAUUGGAAUCACCACCCAUUCCAUCCAGGACUUCUCUUACACUUGGGGGUAGCGGGGUCAGGACAAUCAUCUCAGUCCUGCAUCUUUUCUUCUGCUUUCUUCCCUCCAAGAGCAAAACCUGGGCAAGGGGACUUACUGAGUGGGGGUGGGUGGGGGUUGGGAAAAGGGAAACUGGUGGGAUAUGGAACAUGGCUCUGAGCAGGACUGUUGAGCUCACAUAGUGUUCUGACUCCAAAUCUGGGAGCAGGAGAAUGUGUAAACAAGAAUAAAGUGGAAGCAGGUUGGUGUAGAUCUUAGUCUCAGUGUUCCUGGAGUGAGAGAAGAGGUGCAAGGGGCCCAAAGUCAGGUUGCCAUUUCAGGCGAACUGCCUGGGAAGGAGGAAUGGUGCAGAGUCGGCAAUGGUGUGACUUCAUUCUACAGGAGGUUGGUUAGCAGUGGACAGUUCUAGCUUGUCUUAGAUCAAAACUUAAAGCUGCUUGGGCUCAAGCUGGCAUCUGCCUGUGUCAAGAACUAGGGCCCCCUAAAAACACUCAACUAGUUCUUUCCUUCCUUCACUCCUGGGGUGAGUAGCUUAGUCAAAGCUGCCUAGCCGGUUUGCUAGGCAAGGGCCUCUGGGUGGAGACACCUGAGGAAGCUUUGAGACAGGUAGAUUACAGGUCUCCCAUCCUCAGCCUAGGGGCGAGGGGAGUGGAGGUGGCAGCGGCAGCUGUUUUGGCCUGUGUCUCCCUGAUCGUUCAAGCUCAUACAUGGUUAAUGAUUAAUGAGGCAGUGUGGUGUGGCAGUAUCCAGCUGCCACUUCCUGCCUACUCUGCUGAGUAAACAGGGGCCCUGUCUUAGCUGGGCUUCAAACCUGUUCCCUAGGGAAGGGCUCUGUUCCCUGAAUCACCAGGGAGGAAAGGCAAGGGCAGGGUUGGCAUCUCCUGCUCUUUUGUGAUCCAAGCCUCCUCCCCCGAACCAUGUCUACCCCACAGUAUGACAUCAGCAUGGGGCCUGGGGCUCCUGUUAGCAAAGUUGAAGCUUUCCCCAGGGCCCUAGCAGGAGUCUCCCACUAGCUAGCACAGAGGCUGAGGCCAGAAAGAAAUCACAAACAGAGGGGAGAUGACCUGACUUUUAAUGGCACAGCCCCAGCUCCAGCAAAGCAGCAAGACAGGAAGCUAUGCAAAGCUGCUCAGAGGUGCAGUGGCACAAACAACUCUAGGAGAUCGCCUGUGUUCCCUCCCAUCCCCCAAGCUUAUGACGUGGCUCCAUGCCCAGGAACUCUGGGCCAGCCCAGCCCCACUCCCAAACCCUCAUAAUGCACAGAGGAGCCUGGGCCAAGCCUUGCUUCCAGAGUUGGUAAAUGUAGAGGCAGCAGGAAGAACAGGGUAGCAGUCUAACUUUCAAAGACAGAAACCACUGGAUUAUACUCCUACUUGGAAAGGAGCUGAAGACUCAUCCUUCAACAGUUUGUGCCUGGAUUUUGGUCCUCAUUUCCUCCCUAUACUGAGUAACCCUAGGACUUCAAUUUAAAGUCCCUGGGGUUAUGCUUCCUGGGCCUGGCAAGAACCCCUUUGCAGGUCUCACCUUCAGCGAUGGAAGGGAUAAGGGUCAUGAACAGCAAACAGAGCAGCAGCAGCAUGAAGGGGAAGGCAGCAGAAGCUCAAGCACUCAGAGGGAACAAGAAACCGUGCAAGGAAACUGUUUAUUUCGAAAGGAUUUUGCAAUAAACAUAGUGAAUAGGC